CCUACUUCGACUCCUCUCCCUGUCCCAGGGAGGGGAGAAAAGGUCUGGGAUUCAUUGCCAGGAGGGGCUUCCCCCAGGAUUUCCUACUUCUUUCUUUACUGCUGUGCUUGAAGCUCACAGGAGACCCCUCAAGAGGUGGUCACCGGCCCACAGCCCACCCCAUCCCCCACCCGCCACCCCCACCGUACCAAAUGCUAGCUCUGCCCUUUCUUCUGUGUUUUUCCCAUCAAGAGAGAUGGUUGUGGUCAUGAAGUUCUUCCGAUGGGUUAGACGGGCUUGGCAAAGGAUUAUUUCCUGGGUUUUCUUCUGGAGGCAAAAAAUUAAACCAACCAUCUCAGGACACCCUGACUCCAAGAAACACUCAUUGAAGAAGAUGGAGAAGACUCUCCAGGUGGUUGAGACUUUGAGGUUGGUCGAGCUCCCAAAAGAGGCUAAGCCCAAGUUGGGUGAGUCCCCCGAGCUGGCAGAUCCCUGCGUGUUGGCCAAGACUACAGAGGAGACCGAGGUGGAGCUGGGCCAACAGGGCCAAUCCCUACUGCAGCUGCCGAGGACGGCCGUCAAGUCUGUCUCCACGCUCAUGGUCUCUGCCCUGCAGAGCGGCUGGCAGAUGUGCAGCUGGAAGUCAUCAGUGAGUUCUGCCUCAGUCAGCUCCCAAGUGAGGACGCAGUCACCUUUGAAGACUCCGGAGGCUGAGUUGCUGUGGGAGGUGUACCUGGUGCUGUGGGCCGUUCGGAAACACCUGCGCCGGCUGUACCGCAGGCAGGAGAGGCACAGACGGCACCACGUCCGAUGCCAUGCUGCCCCCCGACCCAACCCGGCUCAGUCCCUGAAACUGGAUGCCCAAAGUCCCCUCUAGGGGGAACCCCAGACCCUUAGAGAGUCCUGACCUCACUCUUACCUGGGGUCCCAUAUCAGCCCCUUCAUUCCAUGUAUUCCAGUUGUAAAACAAGUAUCAAAAUAUUGGGAAAUAAAUAUCAGAUAGUUCUGA